UUACUCUGUGUGAAGAGUCAAGGGUGGAACGAGCCCUGGCUCUUAUUUUCUAAAACAAGAAUUGAGUCUGGCGUUUUGCAGAGCUCUGAAUUGACAGUUAUCACAUCCAUCUUUCAUUUCCACGUCCUUCUAGGGGCAGAGAAAAAGAGUCCUAUUUAAAAAUUUAAACCAAAGCUAUAUUGUCAUAAGCCACUUCUUGAUGAAAUUGUGGCCCCCCCACCUUAAUAUCACUUUCAUAAAUAGGACAUGGGAGGCUUUUCCUCUCGUUUUAUUAUAAAGAUGUGUGUGGGCAAUUAUUUGUCUUAAUUCAUUUUUCUUAAAGUUUUAACUUUUAGCUAAAAUGUCUCUGCUCUAUUGAAAUUAAAACUUCUAACAGUGAAAUCGAAAUCAUUCAUAGACUCUGGUAUUGCAGGGCUGGAACUUUGCAGUGUUCUGAGGUAGUUAAGAGCUUUCCUGGGUUCGCCCCUGGUUUUGCCACUUACUAGCAGUAUGACCUUGAGCAAGUUACUCUGAGGCUCACUUUCUUCUUGUAUUUGAUGGAGAAAAUAAUAGCACUUACCUCUAUAGAGUUAUGAAAAUUUAGUAAGAUAAUUAUGUAUGCAUUUAGCGCUGGAUCUGGCACAUAGUAAACUGUCUAAAACAAGCUGCUAUUUGUUACUCUUAAGCCUAGUUACUUAAAUCAAGAAACAGUUCUUAUAUGAUGUUGUAGGAGAUUCUGGUGAUUCUUAAGUGUUGAUCCCUGUUCAUAAGGCAGUUAUAGUCUUGUUGAGAACUAAGUUUUGUGCAGUUAAAUAAACUAGAAAGUGUACAGUGAAUUACCCAAAGAGUGAUAGAACAAAGAGUACUGACAGUGCUCAGUAACUGGGAAAAAAAUAGUAGUCCAAAGUAGUUGGGCCAGACUUUGAGGAGGAGGUGGCUUGGAGUCUGAAAGUGAGGAAAGAGCGGGAAGGGCAUUUUAUGCUCUUGACAGCUACAAGAGCAGAGUCAGAGGUAUUUGUAACUCUCAGGAAGAUUUGAGUAACAGAAUUACUCUUGAGUAUAUGAUGACAUACCUUUAUUACCAAGUGAUAUCAAAUAUUAGAGCUGACUGUGGUAGUGACAGUUUUUGAUAUAAAUGUGAAAUUGCAUUCUCCCAAAGGAAUCUUGGGUAUGUAUGCACUUUAAAAGAACCCAGAAUCUUGUAAAUAUUGUCACAUGGCUCUUGCAAGUGAUGAUAAUAAAAUGAUGCUCAUAAUAAUGAGGAUUAGCUGCACCCAUCAGCCCAUUUUAGAUUAUGUAUUAUUAGAACACAUUGAGUCCACUUGGGGAAGCCGAUUAAGUCUUUGGCUGCUUUGGUUCCUGAGCAUGAGUUUGUUAAGGUAAAGCAAGUCUUCCUUAAAUACUGUUCCAGGAGUUUCUUUUGACCAGAUGAUUCCUGCUUACUGCUUUGAUCCUGGCUUCAUAUCUUGAUAUUAUAGGUGUCCUAUACUUUUUCUGAGAUUUGUGUGAACUGAAAGUUGAAUAUAAAUCAUAUUUAAAAUGCGUUGGGGUAUGUGAUUAGGGUAAAAGUUGUAGGGGAUGGAUGUCAGUGGCAGGAAGAUUCAAAGUCAAUAUUUUUUCCUUUCUUAGCAAGCUAAGAAUCUACCUUUUGUAACUUCUAGCUAUUGCACCUUCCUUUUCAUCUAGAGGAAUGUUUCCUCCCGAGUGUAUGUGCCGCAAAGUGCUAGUUCUGAAGAUGUCAAUAAGUGUUAUGUAGAAAAAAAGUGGGUGGGUUCUGGGAUGGAAUAAAUGUGGGAAAAACUGGGUUCAACAAAAAUAAACAGUUUUCUUUAAUGCUGGGCUCCUGGAGAUGCUAAUGUGUUUUGAACAUAGUAAAUCUCUAGGGAGUAUGGUUUGGUCCUAAACUUAAUUGAGCUCCCAAGGAACUAGUAUCUUUUUUAGAAAACAGUGCUCUACAGCAGUCACUUUCAUACUCUUCUUUUUUUUUUUGGACCCAGCUUCAUGAUAAGAAAUACAUUUUAACUCAUAAUCAGGAAUUCACAUGUAUCUGAAUAACUGAAGCAAAAGUUUCACAAAAUGUUGAUUACUUUUACUACAAGUGGUAUGCUUGGAUAUUUUCCGCUCUAUUCUGUUUCAUUAAAAAAAAAUGCUGGUUACUCCCCAGCUAAGCUGAUUUUGUGACCCAUUAAAGAGUUGCAAUUCUCACUUGAAAAACACUGUUUCUAGAAUAACUCAGAAAAGUUUAGGGAUGAGAACUAACUUCGUUGUGCAUCACAGUGUGUCAGUCUGUGCCAGGCAGCUUAUAAAUAUUUUUUGCCUCUAAUUUUAUACAUUUAUGAGAUAGGUAUCAUUUUCUAGGUAAGAAAACUAAUCUCUCUCCAAGCAUCAAAUAAUGCGCACUGAAUGAUGGCACCAGGAUUUGAAUCCAGGUCUUUAUACAUCAUAGACUAUGCUGUUCCCACAGUAUUUUGCUUUUUCCAAGUAUAAUGUCCUUUUCACAUGAAUGGCCUCUUCACAUAGUUGAAGACUACUGUGGUGUCACUGCUGACCCUUUCUCCCUGCCACACACUGUGAGCAUUCCCUUCUCUUCUUCAGAGUAAAUAAUCCCAGUUUGUUUUAUCAUUCCUUAGAUAAUGUAAUUCUCUGAUCCUUCGACCAUGGUUAUUUUUUUCUUAAUUAACUCUAAGUUGCUCAUUGUCAUUAUACAUGGUUCCCAGAGUUGUACCCAGCAUUUUAGAUGAUAUUUGGUCAGAUGGAGAGUGUGGUGGGUGUGAAUCAAAUGCUGUUUUUUUUUUAACCAAAUACUUCAUUGACAGUUUUAACUUCUAUUAUGCUUAAUAUGAGCCUGAAGUAUCAACUUCUCUCCCAUAUAUUUUAUACAUAAGAUGUUAAACUGUGUCUUCCUAACCUAGUUUUUGUGUAACGGAUUUUUUUUUUAGCUUAAAUAUAAAGCUUUUAUUUUAUUUUUUUUUAGGCGUGCUCAGAUUAAAUAUAAGGCUUUUAAAUUUCCUUUUGUUAGUUUUUAUUUACACAUUUAAUAUUAUGUUUCUGAGUUAUUUGGUCAUCUUUGUAUUUGGUAGGCAUAUCUACUACGUCUUCAUUCAAAUUGUUGAUAAAAAUAUUAAAUUGACAUAAUAAAUUACUCUGAAGUGGGCAUGUCAGCUAGACUCACUCUGGAUUAAUACCAGUCCAUUAAUCAACACACAUGGUUGUUCAAUAAUUGCUAGUUCUAUCUAUUAUCGUCAGGCCCAUAUAACAUUUUGUGUAGACAUUAUGAUUUUGUAAAGUGCCUUGCUAUAAUUAAGCUAUACUCUGCCUACAAGAUUCUUACCUACAAUGAAGAAUACUACAUUACUAUCACCAACCUAUUAAAAUAGCCAUUGCAGUUGAUUUGUUUGGACUUGUUCAUGAUGAAUGUUCUAGCAUUUCAUGUAUCCACUUUUCCUUUCUUCACAAACUUUUUUUUCAUCCAAUUUUGAAUUUUGCAAGGAAUCAGUUUGGUCUGGACUUUCUAGACACUGCUUAUUUUUCUCUUUAGAAGUCACCAUAUUUCCUUUUAUCCAGACUUUUGAUCCUGCCCGUGUUCACCAUGAUCUUAGUGAUAAAAUUUCUGUUCUUUUCCAUCAUUUGGAGUGGUAGGCCUAAGCCCAUUUUAAGCUACAUUCUGGCUCACUAGAUCAAUUUAUCUUAGGUUUAUGAAGACACUUCAAAUUCAUACUGACUUCUCAUCGAUAACCUUUGUUGAUAAAUGUCCCAAUUCAGAGCUAGGUAGGUAAUGUGGUUUUUAUACUUUUUUGUCACUCGUGGCUCUUCACUGCUGAGAGUUGAUUUAUUGUAUGACCUCUUUGUUUAUGUAUGCUUUUUGUAGAGGGCCAUUGGUAAAAGUUGCCUGUAAUUUAAUUUGGUAAGCCUAAGUUAAUAAAGCAAUUUGUGUAAUUAUCACCACUUAUCUGAAUAGUUUGGCAGUCAUUCACUGAUUAACAUACUAAUAUCUUGGGAAGUUUUAUGUUUUCUAGACUCUUCUGUACCAAGGAGAUGUUACUUUAAAGUAAUGUGGUUUGUGUAUGUGUGUGGGUUAGAUGAAUCAGAAGUUAGACAUCUAAUAAGCUUUCUAUUUCCCUUUUUUUUUUUUUUUUUUUUAAGAGACAGGGUCUUCCCAUGUUGCCCAGGCUAGUCUCAAACUCCUGGGAUCAGGCAGUCUGCCCACCUCAACCUCCCAAAGUGCUAGAAUUACAGGCAUGAGCCACUGUGCCUUGCCCUCUAUUCCAUUGUUAGCAGUGGUUUUCCAGUCAUUCUAAAAUGGCUUUAAUUUUUUUUCUUUAAUGGAACAAAUACUUAGAGUACCUGUGUGCAGCACAGUGUUGGGAACAUUGAGAGACAUGAUAAUGCAAGUUCUUAAAAAAUAGAACUUGGCCAAGCAGAGCCUCAUGGUUGAUAAAAGUAUAUUGCAGUCACUGUGGUGUGCCCAUGUUUUUAUAUGCCAAGCAUUUUGCAAGACAGCAGUCCGCAACCUUUUUGGCAUCAGGGACCGGUUUCGUGGAAGACAAUUUUUCUGUGGACCAGGGGUGGGGGUAUAAUCUACAGCUCACUGCAGCUUCAGUACCACCCCCCCUCCCCCACCCCUGGCUCAAGUGAUUGUCUUACCUCAGCCUCUUGAGUAGCCAGGACCACAGGCGCGUGACACCAUGCCUGGCUAAUUUAUUUUUUAUGUUUUGUAGAGAUAGGGUCUCACUAUGUUGCCCAGGCUGGUCUCGAACUCCUGGGCUCAAGUGAUCCACCUGCUUCACCCUCCCAAAGUGUUGGGAUUAUAGGCGUGAGCCAUCGUGCUCAGCUCCUUUACACAUGUUAAAUCAUUUAAUGUGUACAAUUUGGAGUUGUAAUUAUUAUUAUUUUUAUUGUAAAAUAUAACAAAAUUUACCAUGUUAAUAAUUUUUAAGUUUACAGUUCAGUGGCAUUAAGUACAUUCACAAUGUUGUGCAAUCAUCGCCACCAUCCAUCUCUAGACCUUUCAUCUUCCUCAAUUGAAACUGUGUACCCAUUAAACAGUUUCCCUGUUUCCAUGGACGCCAGCCCCUGGCAACUACCAUUCUGCUUCUCUGUCUAUGAAUUUGACCACUCUAGGUAGCUUGUGUAAGUAGAAUCAUACAAUACUUGUCUUUUUGUGUCUGGCUUAUUUCAUUUAGCAUUAUGUUUUCACAGUACAUCCAUGUGGUAGAAUGUGUCAUUUUAUCCCCAUUUUACAGCAAAAGAAACUAAACCCAAAGUCGCAUAGCUAAUAAAGUGAAAUUGAGAUUGACACCAAACCUAAAAGUCAAGUCUGAUGAAGUACGAUUGAUCUUGAUUUAUUUAGCCUAUAGAUAUUUAGCUUGGGGAAGAGAACUUUUUGAGUAUUUGAAGGACUCUAAUAAGGAUUAUUACUUAUAUAACUAACUGUUCAUCGCUAGACUAAUAGGUGUAAAUUAGAGGCAGGCAAAUUUUGUUUUAGUAGAAGGAAGAAUUUUUUAAUAGAGCUGUUUUUGGAUGAUAUGCACUACCCUAAAAAAAUUGUUGGAAAUAACCUUCAAAAGACUGCUGAAUGCUCCUGUGGCAGGCGAUGUUACAAAGAAGUAAAAAAGUUGAAUUGGGUGAAUUCUGAGUGUUCUUUUAAUUCUGUUGCACUCUAUGUGGGAGCAUAAGAAACCUUCAAGACAGGCUGGGCAUGGUGGCUCAUGCCUGUAAUCCUAACACUUUGAGAGGCCAAGGCAGACAGAUCACUUGAGGUCAGGAGUUCAGAACUAGCCUGGUCAACAUGGUGAAACCCUGUCUCUGCUAAAAAUACAAAAAUAUUAGCUGGGCAUGGUGGUGGGCGCCUGUAAUCCCAGCUACUUGGGAGGCUGAGGGAGGAGAAUUGCUUGAAUCCGGGAGGCAGAGGUUGCAGUGAGCUGAGAUCACGCCAUUAUACUCCAGCCUGGGCGACAGAGCAAGACUCUGUCUCAAAAAAAAAAAAAAAAAGAAGAUACCUUUAAGACAGAGUGCUAAGCUUAAGUGUGAGGAGAUAUUUAGCAGCGGAAGCAUCAUGAAUGUUUUCCCUUUAAGUCUGUGGCACAUUUCUCUGAAUAUCCUCAGUAAUGGCCAGUUGUUUUCCUCUUGAGGGUAGGUUUGAAUUUUGAAAACCAUUAGAAGUCAUUAUCUUGCCUGGUGAAUAAAAAUGAGUUAGCAGGGUAUUUAAAAGUCCUCAGCAGUCCAGCGCUAAUUUACUUUUUUCCUAGAUUUACUUGCUUUUGCCAGAACCUUCAAGAACAUUUAUGCCCUUUGGCUUUUGAUGUUCAUCUGUUUUUUUCUCUUCCUCCUCUUACCAAAAUUUUACUUAUUCUUCAGGCACAAUGCAGAUUUUCUUUCCUUUGUGAAAUUCUCCUGAAUUUUUAACUUGGUUUACUUCCUCUUCAUUGUUAACCUAUCACUGUUUAUAUACCCUUUUUUAGAGUAUAUUUAACGCAACCACCUUGUGCUUUGGUCUGUGUAGUCUAGAAUGUGAGCAGUUUAAGCAGAAGGAUAGUAGCAUAUUCAUCUUUAUGUUUCUGAACAGGACCACAGUGUAGUAAGAGUUCAGUGACAUUAAUUUAAAUGAAAUCAAUCUAUCAGUGAUGUUAGGUUAAAAUGAGGCAAAACUGUAAAACAGUGAGACCAGAUUUCUUACAUGACGCUUAUGCCAGUUACAGAUGAGAUACUUCACAGAUUCUGAAUAAUGGCAGUAUUGAAUGUAUACUUUCCCAUGAUGAAUUAAAGAAGAAAAUACUGUCUAGAUGUAGUGUGUGAUUUUUAAAAUAAGUUUAAAAAUUAGCCAAAAUACUGGCAUCGCUCUGUUUAGUAGGAUUACAGAAGCACUUUGUUUUAAACUUCUUUGUACUUUUUGUGAUUUCCAAGUUUUCUGAUAAGACAUGAAUUGCUUUUAGAAUUUAAAAAAUCCUAUUGAUAAAAUUUAAGUCAGUUUUAUUACUCUGUGAUCAUGUGGGGAUCAUAAUAUAACAUGAUACAUUAGAAGCCUUUUUACUUGUAGUUUUCCUUGUUACUUAGUAGUAGUAAGAUUAUAUAUCACAGAUGGAUACAUUUUGGCUUCAACAAAUAUGGUUUCAUUUAUUGAGUAACUGCCAUAGGUGGAGCACUGUGCUGUAAUGAUAGCACAUUUUUGAUAGAAUUGGAACCCAAGAUAUGUAUUUGAUCUUAUGAUCUAUUAUUCUUGUUUGUUUUAAAUUUAACAAUUUAAUUGGGCAAAAAAAACAUUUAUUGAACUGGGUAGCACCCAGGACCGAAAGUGAUUUAGAAUGCUUCUUAGAAUGUUCUUAACUUUACACUUAAAAAAUUAAAUUCCACAAGUGUAACUAUUAAAACAUUUAUCAGAUCUACCUAAAUAAAUCAUGUAGUCUGUUUUCAUGAAAAACACAACUUUGGUUUUUAGGAAUAUCAGAUAAGGAACACCAAAGUUGUAUAGCUCACAUCCUGUGAGCCUUCUGGAUCACUGAUGUUGCUACUGCUCCUCAGUCCCCAUCUUUGGGGCCUCCGUGUAUUCAAAUUCCUAUGCCAGAUUGCCCAGGGAACCUGGUGCUGAUACCCUGGUAGCCCAAAAAGGCUACUUGCCUUCUACUUCCACUUACGCAGACCCCUGCCUCCUUACCCUUCUGCUAGGAACAUAUCUAUAACUAUAUAAAUUCAUGUAAUUUUGACAUUAUUUUUUAAAAUGGCAAUUUGGGCAGUAAAUAGCAGAAUUAAGUAGUGUCUUAAUAUAAAUGGUUUGCAUUACCUGAAUACACUAUUCCUUGUAGUAAUUAUCUGUACUACCCAGAGCACAUUGCAUGUGACUCCUGUUGGGCUAAUUUUCAGUAGCAAAAAUGAAUUUGUAAAAUAAUGUAGGUUUUAAGGCUUUGGUAAUAAUAAGUUCUUAUUUCACCUCUUUCAUUUACUCAAAAUUACGUCUUCUGAGAUCUUUUGGGAUCGAAGUUAUGGAGGAAAUGAACAACUUUAGGACAAACUAGCUUAUUUAAGAGGAAGGCUUUAAACUAGGUCUUUAGGAGUGGCUCAGAAAUUGCAGAACAGUUUACUUUGAUCUGGGAAAGGUCUCACAUUCUGGAAUAAAAUAGAAAUUAGAGACUUUAGAGAAAAAAAUAUUGAUUCUAUCUCCUUGAAAUAUGAAGAAUAAUAGAUGCAAUAUAAUGUAGUACCACGGUAUCAGAUAUGAAAUUCUUGAAAGUAUUUGGAAAGAUAAGACAAAGGAAGUUGUAUUUAGUUAAAAAUCAGGUUUAUAAUUCAUGAGGAUGAAUCAAAUCAUCUCCCACUUCUGCAGUGUACUAGACUGAAACUCCUCCCCCACACAUCCCUCUCCUACUCCAUUCAGGAGCUUCUGCUCCUCUCUCUGUGAGACAGUAAGAAAGUACCCAAUUAUGUGUGGCUCUUGAGGCUUAUUUUGUUUGAAAAGUGUGAAUGAGAACCAGGAGUGGGCCAAGCUAGUCUGUAAGUGACCCUUGACUCCAAUAAGCUUGAGGAAUGGGAUUUAAUAGGUACUCUCAAGUUAGGUUUUUAGUAUGCAUUUAAUACCUAAUCGGUACUAUAUUCUAUAGUGAUAAUCAGACUAAAUUGUGUGUUUUUGCUAAUACCUAUUUAGUAGAUACAGAAAGAGUACUUUAGUAAUUUUAGGCUUUGAAUGCUUAUAUCUUUUGAGUGGGCCUGCUCAUUUCUCCUCUGAGUGGGAGAUAAUGAAUCUUGUGUUGACCUGUCACAGUGAAACUCUUAUUUGCCAUUGGUUAUACUUAGGACUGAUGGUGGAGUGGAUUAAGAAGCAAAACCCAAAAAACUGAUGAAUCCUAGAAACCUGAAUCUAGAGGUUUGGAACUUGAUGAGCAGGCACGGCUGUAUUCAUCACCAAAGAAAAAACUUACACCAAUGCAGAAAUCGGUUAGUCCAUUAGUUUGGUGCAGGCAAGUUUUGGAUUACCCAAGUCCUGAUGUUGAGUGUGCUAAAAAAUCUCUUAUCCACAAACUUGAUCAAACUAUGUCAGCUCUCAAGAGGCAGAAUUUAUAUAAUAAUCCUUUCAACUCUAUGAGUUACACCAGUCCUUACAGUCCAAAUGCCAGUAGCCCAUACAGCAGUGGCUUCAAUUCUCCAUCCUCAACCCCAGUGCGACCUCCUAUAGUCAAACAGCUUAUACUUCCUGGAAAUUCAGGUAACUUGAAAAGCUCAGACAGAAAUCCUCCACUCAGUCCUCAGUCCUCUAUAGAUAGUGAGUUAAGUGCUUCAGAAUUAGAUGAAGAUUCAAUUGGAUCCAAUUAUAAGCUAAAUGAUGUAACUGAUGUACAGAUUCUAGCCCGGAUGCAGGAAGAAAGUCUCCGGCAAGAAUAUGCAGCCACCACGUCUCGGCGCAGUUCUGGUUCAUCUUGCAAUUCUACAAGACGGGGUACUUUUAGUGAUCAGGAACUUGAUGCACAAAGUUUAGAUGAUGAAGAUGACAAUAUGCAUCAUGCAGUAUACCCUGCUGUUAACAGGUUUUCACCAUCACCACGCAAUUCACCUCGACCGUCACCUAAGCAGUCACCCAGAAAUUCACCUCGUUCACGAUCUCCUGCUCGGGGAAUAGAAUAUAGUAGAGUGUCCCCACAGCCUAUGAUUAGCCGCUUACAGCAACCUCGCCUUUCACUUCAAGGCCAUCCCACAGAUUUACAGACAAGCAAUGUUAAAAAUGAAGAAAAACUAAGACGCAGUCUUCCAAACCUGUCCCGAACAUCUAAUACACAAGUUGACUCAGUGAAAAGCAGCAGAAGUGACUCAAAUUUUCAAGUGCCAAACGGAGGAAUACCUCGUAUGCAACCUCAGGCUUCAGCCACUUCGCAAAGGCUGAAAAAUUUGCCUCGCACUUCCCUCAAAGCCAAACAGUUGCUUCAAACUUCAUCUACAAAAAGAGUACCUUCUCCAGGCAAAUUCCGUUCCCCUGCAGCACCAUCUCCUUUGGCUCUUCGGCAACCAGUGAAAGCAUUUAGUAACCAUGGCUCUGGUUCUCCUGGUAGCCAAGAAAUAACACAGCUCACACAAACCACCUCCUCACCUGGGCCUCCUAUGGUUCAGAGCACAGUCUCAGCAAAUCCUCCCAGCAAUAUCAACAGCGCUACUCUAACCAGACCUGCAGGGACAACUGCAAUGAGAAGUGGCUUGCCCAGACCCAGUGCCCCUUCUGCUGGGGGCAUACCAGUGCCUCGCAGCAAACUUGCACAGCCUGUUCGCAGAUCCUUGCCAGCUCCUAAAACCUAUGGUAGCAUGAAAGAUGACAGUUGGAAAGAUGGCUGUUACUGACCAGCAAAGACAAGAAUGCAGAAGUCCACGGCUUCAUGGAUACCCUUCACCAGGCUAAAAAACAACUUUUAUAUGCAGACUGUUCAGAUAAGACUCUUGGGAUUUAUAAAAUCCCAGCCCUCUCUGUCUUAAUUAGCACAAACCGACAGAGAUCAUCAAACAGCACUUUAAUGACAUUUAACAUCAGAUGUGUUUGGUAAUCAUACAAUCACUCUCCAUAGAAUCACUUUUAGUUUUGUUUAAUAGAAACUAGGUUGAUUUUUAAAAAAUAUUUGACAGAGGCCAAUAUCUGGGCAAAUACCUAAUGGAUGCCAAAGAGAAAUGCCCAUUUGUAAAUGAGAAAAAUGCCCAUUUGUGCACAAGAAAAUGGUGAAUUCAGGCUAUCCAAAACUUCACAUUCAACCUAAUUUACUGUAUAAAUAGUAUCAAUAAAUAUUUGUGUUAAUGAGAACUAAUAUUCUGACUAAUUAUCUAAAGUGUUUCACUAGUACACCAGGAAACUACAGAUUGAGAUUAGGGGGUGGGAGGAAAGAAACCUGGGCUAGAGAUUAAAACAUUCCUAAAUUUAGCAGAAUUUCAGAAAUGAUUUUUGCAGAUUCAUUAGAAAAGAAAAAUUGUCAUUUAAUCUUAAGUUUUGGAUGUAGCUCACAUGUCACCACCACCAGAUAGUGUUACAGCAUGUAUCCAUCAUGUUGCAUUGACACAUCAAACUUGUGUGUGUUUGUUUUGAUUGCCAAAAGGGCUUAAUAUCAGUUGUACAAUCUUUCUGAACUUUAUAGUUCCUGGCUCAGGAAAGAUGGCCUUUGCUAUUGAAGCCAACUUCUUCACAUGCUGUUAUCUUUACAGAACUAAGAGAUCUUGUUUCUAUUAGCAGGUUUUCAUGAUAGGAAAGAACAAGUAGUGUGUGUCUUUAUUCUUGAUACAACACCACCUCGGUGCUUGCAACCUGGAACAAAACCAUACCAUGAGAGAGAGGGGGAAAAAAAUCUAUGCACUUAACCUACAAAAUCUCUGGUGAUGACAGUUGUAUUGUUGCUAUUACAUGGCAUAACGGUCUAUUAUGUGGUAGGAAAAUAUAGCCUGCUAAAUCCUACUUAAGUUGAUCCACUUUAAACUGAGUAACUGUAUAAAACAUCUAUUGAAAAUUCUUUUCCUUUUGACUUAGAUUCUGCCUUACAUCAAUUUUUGCAUUUUUGGUAAAAAAAAAACCCUACUACGUAUGACUCUAACCUGAUACUUGCUCUCUAAUGGCUCUUAAUAUAUCCUUGAAAUCGGCUAUUUCAAUUUUAUCAGACUUUUACCAGAGUAAAACUUGCUUCUGUAGCAGGCCUCUCAUUUUUUAUUAUGAGGUCUGUUUUUAAAUACUUAAUUUGAACAGCUCUAAGAUAUUGUCACUUAGGUCAUCUAAAAGCUUUUAGAGAUUUGAACAUAAGUUCAUUUCCUGUUAAUCAAAGACAUUCCGUAAGUUGGCAAAAGAAAUUGGGAGAGAGAAAUAGAAGGCUUGAUAUUCUGGACAGCAUUAAGGUUGAUAGGUUGAUGAUAAAAACUUAAAACCAGGACCUCCAUUCUGUCAUGACUGACACCAUGGUAGUCUGUCAGCUUGACCAGUGGAGAGUCAUUCAUUUAGCACAAGCAGCUGGAGAUUUAAACUGCCAGUACUAUGUAUUUGGUGUAUAAUGCAAGGAAGAAACUUUAUCCUUGAAUUUGAGGGUGAUGGGGUGGGUCAGGAAAGGAUGGCGCCAGAAUUCUACAUGAUAAUGAACUAAAAAAUGUUGCUUUUCAGAGGAAGAUAAAGCAUCUUCUUUUGGGAGGGGGGUAUCUCAUGUCUAAGUAAGUAAAAGAAAGAAGUAGCUACUGUCUCUUUUAAAAACCACGUACAAAACAGAACAAGUCUCAGUUUUCAGUGCAACAUUUCAAAAAAUAUAUAUGCUGCAAUCUAAUAAUUAAAAGGAAUUUUACCUAUUAUGAAACAUAUUACAUUUUUUAAGUUAGAUAAUCAGUUUCAAAAGGAGUAUUCAGGUUAUUUAACUUUGUUUUUAAAUGGCUGCAUCAGAAAAAAAUGUCUAUUUUUUUUUAUUAAAAUAUUUCAUCACUUGUUAAAACAUAUUUUUGAUCUGAGUUUGGUAAAGUAUUAUUUUACCUGCUGUUGUACUACCACAGACUGUUGACUUUUAGUUUCUUAAAGAGAAAAAUUGCCUUUUUACUAGAAAGCCUUUGUAUAUUGCAAUUUUUCUGUUUGGGAAAAUCUAAGGAUUUACUGUGGUUAGUCUUACAGAAGAAAUGUGGAUUUGAUAAACUAGUGCCUAUGAUUUUAACUUAUGUUUGAUAUAUAGUAGUAAGGGUUUUAUGAAUGUUGAUUAUUUUGUGCCAACAGCCCAGAAUUGUCACUUAUAUGUAAGCAGAAAACAAUGAGCUCUGCUUCCAAAGUUAUUUAAUUUUCUCAGUGUUUGAAUGUUAUUUUUUGUAAGUGUGUUAAUAAAAGUGUAAAGAAUUGGAAAAAAUAUAAAUAUUCUUAACUCAAGCAUUUGCUGGAUCAUUUUUCUACAAAACUUGUUUGUACAAUAUAAAACACUCUCUGAAGAGUUGACUUUUUUUCAGUUUCGUAUCCUGGAAAUCACAUUUUGUAAAACUGGGGACCAUUCAUAAUUGUCAGAUACUUUUUAAAAUUAUCUCAAUACAUCACUUUUAUAAAAAAAAAAAGUUUUUUUGAAAGAAAAUUAGAUACAUAUGUGGCCCCAGAUGUUUGUAUAACUCUAGAAUGAUCUAGACUAUGUAUGUUUAAAUUAACUUUUUAUUGAAUGUACAGGUGUCCAUUUUUGACGUUAAGCAUGGUCCUUUAAGGUCACAUGACGUUUGAUUUGCAAACAUUUCUAUAGCCGAACUUGUAUAUGUGGUUGCCUCCUUAAUAAACAGCCUGACCAUAAUGUUUAUUAUUAAAUUUAUAUUCUUUAAGUGUUUAAUUAAUCUCUGGAUAUGGUAAGAUUCCUUUUUUCCUCUCAGUUGCCUACACUUGGUUUUAAUAAAUUACUCAGUUGAGUUUUUCUUUAACCACAGAAACCCAAAUCAUAUUGCCCUUUCAGAUUUAGUCUUCAUGGGGUUGGAUUAUGUCUUAUAUUUUCUCUGUCAGAGUUAUUUCAUAUAUGGAUUUUACUUGAAGGAAAUUUACAGUUUACUCUAAAUUGAUUUGUUCUUGGAACUUUUUUACCUGCUGUGAAUUGAUACCUAGUUAUAAAAAGCUAGCAUUUGCCUAGAUCAUAACUAUGUAUGGUAUCUAGUUAGAAAAAAACAAGCAAAAAGCUAUUAUGAGUUUCCAAGAGGGACAAUUAAUGCAUUUUCAUACCAAAUGCGAAUAUUUAGGUGAUCACGUGCAUCUUUUCUUGUAUGGAUGGAAAAAUCAAGAAUUGUACACUGUUUAAUGAGUUCUCCAUAUUCCUUUAGGAGAUAUUUGCUUUGCAAUUACAUGUUACAAUUAGAAUAAUUACAAUUAAAAUAAUAUUACAUGUUACAAUUAGAUUAAUAGUGAUGAGAGGGAAAAAAGACACCCUUCUGUUUUUUUCUCUCAAGCCAGUCUAAAAACUUGAAGAGCCAUUUAAAAUUAAAUGUCACUAUACUUGUAUUAUAAAUCAAUACAUAAGUUUAAACCUGUUAUAUACUCAGUGCAACAGAAAAACCCAUAUGGAGGUUCAACCACUGAUGUAUUUUGAAUGAUCCUAAAUAUAAGUCUUGGGUGGCUAAAUGGCCCUCUGCUUACCAGUCUGAAAAUGAAACCGAUUAUACUCAUCGGCCUUAUUUACUGUAAUACAAACUGGUUAAAACUAUGUUAACUGAAUGCUAGUUUGAAACAAAUUAUCUACAUUAAGUCAUCUUAAUGUUUUCUCUUUAAAAGAAAUAAAAAAAUCUGUUUCUUCUGAUUUCGAAAGUAAUAGAAACUCUGCUGUAGAACAUAAACUAAAAAUAUUAAAAAGUAUAAAGGUAAAAAAUGAUAGUUGUCUGCAAUCCCAUAAUCCGGAAAUAUUGAAGUACUGUCCGUAACAUGGUUAUGACAUGUUAAGUGGAAGGGUAGAAGGUCUUUUUUUUUUUAAGGAGAAAAUGUUUCUUUUAAAUAAAUGUUUCUUAUGUAAAAA